ACUGCCCUCGCUUCCUGUGCCUCUUCAGGUCAUCGCUUGCUCUCGUUCCCAGGCUUUGGCUUCUAGUGGACGAGAAUCACCGAGUCUGCGGGGCUGGAUGCUGACCGCCCGGACCAGCACCUAGGCGGGCGGGAGCUGUGCGGCCCAGGGUUCGCGCGGGCCGGGUAGAGGCUCGAGCUGGGACCCCCGAGCGUGAACCCCGGAGCCGGCGGCGCUGGGGCCAGAGGGGCCGGGAGCCCCAGGGAGGCGGAUCUGGGCCCCGAGAAGGACACCCGCCUGGAUUUGCCCCGUAGGCCCGGCCCGGGCCCCUCGGGAGCAGAACAGCCUUGGUGAGGUGGACAGGAGGGGACCUCGCGAGCAGACGCGCGCGCCAGCGACAGCAGCCCGCCCCGGCCUCUCGGGAGCCGUGGGGCAGAGGCUGCGGAGCCCCAGGAGGGGGCCAGUGUCAUUCAAAGAUGUGGCUGUGGAUUUCACCCAGGAGGAGUGGCGGCAACUGGACCCUGAUGAGAAGAUAACAUACGGGGAUGUGAUGUUGGAGAACUACAGCCAUCUAGUUUCCUUGGCUUAUGAGGUGGCAACAUCUUGUACUUCGGAGAUUCUGAAGCCGAGCAACUUGCCCAAGUCCUUCUUCUUUUCCCAUUAACAAGAUAUGAUAUCACCAAGCCAAACGUCAUCAUUAAGUUGGAGCAGGGAGAGGAGCUGUGGAUAACGGGAGGUGAAUUUCCAUGUCAACAUAGUCCUGGGAUCGUGGGACUUUACCAGAUCGGUUUGUAAUAACACCUCGAAGACGCUAUCCGAUCCAUCAGACCCAGUAUUCCUGUCCGGGGGUACUUCCCACAGUGUGCUGGAAUGGUUAUCACAAGAAGGCUGUGCUGUCCCCUCGCAACUCCAGGAUGGUGUGUAGCCCAGUGACUGUGAGGAUCGCCCCUCCUGACAGAAGAUUUUCACGUUCUGCGAUACCAGAGCAGAUAAUCAGCUCAACACUGUCGUCACCAUCAAGUAAUGCCCCAGACCCAUGUGCAAAGGAGACUGUACUGAGUGCCCUCAAAGAGAAGAAGAAGAAAAGGACAGUGGAGGAAGAAGACCAAAUAUUCCUUGAUGGCCAGGAAAAUAAAAGAAGGCGCCAUGAUAGCAGUGGCAGUGGACAUUCAGCAUUUGAGCCCCUGGUGGCCAGUGGAGUCCCCGCUUCUUUUGUGCCUAAGCCUGGGUCUCUGAAGAGAGGCCUCAAUUCUCAGAGCUCAGAUGACCACUUGAAUAAGAGAUCCCGAAGCUCUUCCAUGAGCUCCUUGACAGGCGCUUACACAAGUGGCAUCCCUAGCUCCAGCCGCAAUGCCAUUACCAGUUCCUACAGCUCCACUCGAGGCAUCUCACAGCUGUGGAAGAGAAAUGGCCCCAGUUCAUCACCCUUCUCUAGCCCAGCCUCAUCCCGCUCCCAGACACCGGAGAGGCCAGCAAAGAAAAUAAGAGAAGAAGAGCUGUGUCAUCAUUCCAGUUCUUCAACUCCAUUGGCAGCAGACAAGGAGUCCCAGGGAGAAAAGGCUGCAGAUACAACCCCAAGGAAGAAACAAAACUCGAAUUCUCAGUCUACACCUGGCAGCUCUGGGCAGCGUAAGCGGAAAGUUCAGCUGCUGCCUUCUCGGCGAGGGGAACAGCUGACCUUGCCUCCACCUCCCCAGCUUGGCUAUUCGAUCACUGCCGAGGACCUAGACUUAGAGAAGAAGGCUUCAUUACAGUGGUUCAACCAGGCCUUGGAGGACAAGAGUGAUGCUGCCUCGAACUCUGUCACUGAGACCCCACCUACCACUCAGCCUUCAUUUACCUUUACCCUGCCUGCUGCUGCAACUGCCUCCCCACCCACCUCCCUCCUGGCCCCAAGCACCAACCCACUGUUAGAGAGCUUGAAGAAGAUGCAGACUCCCCCGAGCCUGCCACCCUGCCCAGAAUCUGCUGGAGCAGCAACCACUGAGGCCCUCUCACCUCCAAAGACACCCAGCCUCCUACCCCCGCUGGGUUUAUCACAGUCAGGGCCGCCAGGGCUGCUCCCCAGCCCCUCCUUUGACUCCAAACCCCCGACCACUUUGCUGGGGCUGAUCCCUGCUCCAUCCAUGGUACCAGCCACUGACACCAAGGCACCUCCAACCCUUCAGGCAGAGACGGCUACCAAACCCCAAGCCACAUCUGCCCCGUCCCCCGCCCCCAAGCAAAGCUUCCUGUUUGGAACACAGAACACCUCACCUUCCAGCCCUGCCGCCCCUGCUGCAUCUUCAGCAUCUCCCAUGUUCAAGCCCAUUUUCACGGCUCCACCCAAGAGUGAGAAGGAAGGCCUCACACCGCCUGGCCCUUCAGUCUCAGCCACAGCGCCCUCCAGCUCCUCCCUCCCCACGACCACCAGCACCACAGCCCCGACCUUCCAGCCUGUCUUUAGCAGCAUGGGGCCACCUGCAUCUGUGCCCUUGCCUGCUCCCUUCUUCAAGCAGACAACUACUCCCGCCACUGCUCCCACCACAACUGCCCCGCUCUUCACUGGCCUGGCCAGCGCCACCUCUGCUGUGGCUCCCAUCACCUCUGCCAGUCCAUCCACAGACUCUGCUUCGAAGCCUGCGUUUGGCUUUGGCAUAAACAGUGUGAGCAGCAGCAGUGUGAGUACCACGACCAGCACCGCCACUGCCGCCUCACAGCCUUUCCUCUUCGGGGCGCCCCAGGCCUCUGCUGCCAGCUUCACCCCGGCCAUGGGCUCCAUAUUCCAGUUUGGCAAACCUCCUGCCUUGCCCACAACCACCACAGUCACCACCUUCAGCCAGUCCCUGCCCACUGCCGUGCCAACGGCCACCAGCAGCAGCGCUGCCGACUUUAGUGGUUUUGGCAGCACCCUCGCCACCUCCGCCCCGGCCACCAGCAGCCAGCCCACUCUGACGUUCAGUAACACGAGCACCCCCACGUUCAACAUUCCCUUUGGCUCAAGCGCCAAGUCCCCGCUCCCAUCAUAUCCGGGAGCCAACCCCCAGCCCGCAUUUGGGGCCGCUGAGGGGCAGCCACCGGGGGCCGCCAAGCCAGCCCUUACCCCCAGCUUUGGCAGCUCUUUCACUUUUGGAAACUCUGCAGCCCCGGCCCCGGCUACUGCACCCACACCUGCACCUGCGUCCACGAUCAAGAUCGUGCCUGCGCACGUGCCUACGCCCAUCCAGCCUACCUUUGGCGGUGCCACGCACUCGGCGUUUGGAUUGAAAGCCACGGCUUCCGCCUUCGGCGCUCCCGCCAGCUCACAGCCCGCCUUUGGCGGCUCCACUGCUGUCUUCUCCUUCGGUGCAGCCACCAGCUCCGGCUUUGGAGCCACCACCCAGACCGCCAGCAGCGGGAGCAGCAGCUCGGUGUUUGGCAGCACAACACCAUCACCCUUCACGUUUGGGGGUUCGGCAGCCCCCGCUGGCAGUGGGAGCUUUGGGAUCAACGUGGCCACCCCAGGCUCCAGCGCCACCACCGGAGCUUUCAGCUUUGGAGCAGGACAGAGUGGGAGCACAGCCACCUCCACCCCCUUCACAGGGGGCUUAGGUCAGAACGCCCUGGGCACCACCGGCCAGAGCACACCGUUUGCCUUCAACGUGGGCAGCACAACUGAGAGCAAACCUGUGUUUGGAGGCACCGCCACCCCCACCUUUGGUCAGAACACCCCUGCGCCUGGAGUGGGCACAUCGGGCAGCAGCCUCUCCUUUGGGGCAUCUUCAGCACCCGCCCAAGGCUUUGUUGGUGUUGGACCGUUCGGAUCGGCGGCCCCUUCAUUUUCCAUUGGUGCGGGAUCCAAGACCCCAGGGGCUCGACAGCGACUGCAGGCCCGAAGGCAGCACACCCGCAAAAAGUAGCCUUUGUCCCCUGUCCCUGUUCCCCCCACCCCUUCCCUAAAUCUGGACCUUGGCACGUGCUAGAAAGAGCCUUGGACCCUUCCAGCUGCGUAAAGCAAACCUACCCCGGAUCUCUGGCUUCAGCCGCCAGGGGGCAGUGGCAGCCCUGGGGCCCUUUCCCUUCUGGAGGAAGCACAAGCCUCAGGGAAGGGGAAGCAGGAUGCGGAGGGCCAAAGCCCGGGACCUCUACUUGAACAGUUCCACUGGGGAGGCUGGAGAACUAAGGACCUGUACAUAGUGUCCGCUGCCCUGACUCCCGCUUAGCGCACCCUUAGGCAGGCGCCCCUUCCACCUUUCCCCGAGAGCCGUCGUCGCUGGAGGGGGCAGGGUCCAGCCCGCCUGGAUCGGUGGUGUGCACCUGAUGGGAUUUGGGAAAUGGGUUAUCCCUAAAGCUUUAUCUUGCUUGGCUUAGCUGUGAGAAGUGGUUCUCUUCCUCUGGUCCCUUCUGGGGACUCUGUUUCCCCAUUUCUUGCUGCUGUGUCCCUCACCGGUUCCUUGCAGGAUUCCCUCCUUUUUAAAUGCCCUUGAAUCUAGCUUUGCCUUGGAGACCCCAGUGGGUGCUGCUCCUGCCGUUUUCUUCCUGCCAAGCCUGAAUCAAUGUUUCAUCUCCAACCCUCUGCCAGUUUGGCCCCUCAGAGCUUGGUGGCUCAAGACUGUUAGCCUGGCAGAGCCAGGGGUGAAGGGAGAAGCUCUUGGAGCAGGCAGGAUGCCCACUGCUGCUUCAGCUGCCUCCUCGCCCAGCUACCCUUUGGCCCCAUUGGGCCCUCGUCUGCCUCUCCAGGAUUGUAUGUUUCAAGCCUUGUCCUGUGUUCCUUUGUCUGACGCUCUGUGUAUUGCUCUUUGAAUCGAGUUUGGAGGAAGAGUUGAGUUGUAUGAGUGGCGGCAUGUUGGUAGUGCCGGACUUCCUGUUUCAAGUUUUCUGGGGCCUCGCUAAUUGAAUGUGGAAAGUAGCACCACUUGACGGCUACAAGUGCCGACUCCUGAAUUUUCCCAUGGUGUUCUGACUUCAAGGGCUGGCAGCCAGGGAGAAUGGGCCCAGGGGAAGCAAAGACCUCUUCCCUCUGCGGUUUCUGUCCCACUUAACUGACCUCACUGGAGGCUACGUCACCCAAAGUAGAUGUUAGAAAACCUAAAUUAAUGAACCAUAUUUUUAAAAUCCUAUUUUUCCCAAACAGGGCCCUCUGCAGCCCAUCCUUUCCUUCCGUCCUUCUGAAACCACAUACCCCAGGCCCAAGCGCCUUGCUGUCACGCCCAACCUCUUUGGGAGAAGUAUGAAUGCGUGUGUCUAAAUUAAAAGAAAAAAAUAUUUAAACGUUUUUUAACAAAAAUUUAUUUUUGUAUUUAAGCUAAAUUGCCUUUUAAAUUCCUUCAAGCUUGGUUCAUUGAGGUGGUUAAGUAUAAAUGCUAUUAACUAGGAAUUAGCUGUAUAGUUAAGUUAUGCCUGUGCAAAGAAGAGGCUCAAAUGCUGUCCCCGGCAGCUUUCCUGGGGGACUAGAGCUCCUUCUGGCCAUGUUAUAUGAAAUGUAAUUCUUAUUUUAUAAAUAAUGUGAUGUAGAUGUAACCGGUGCCCCCUCCCCGUUGUGACUGAGGGCGAGUGUUAUACCUGGCUGCGUGUGCAGCUGAGGAGGGAGUGAACCUCAAGCCUAAAUACCUGUUAGGAUUGGAGGGUCUGGGUGGGCCUGGGCCUAGCAAUCAAGCUUCUACCUGUACCUUAUGUAAGGUAGACCCUCCUAGUGUCAGUACCUGAGCUUGUUUACCUCAGUUCCGCAGGCAGGACAGCCGGUCCGGGAACCCUGAGUGAGAGUGAGUGUGGAUGUGUACAGUACACACACUGGACGGCAGCGGGAGGCUGGGACUUUCCAUUACAAAUAGAGACUUCAUUCCUGUUGAGUCUAGUUGGAAUUUUUAGUAUGAAUGUGAGAUUUUUCUCCUGCUUGUGACAUUAAGAAUAAAAAACUGUGAUCUAUCGUA